AGGGCUUCCUGGCUGCAGUGGCUGCUGCCCCAUCCCAGGGCCGCGGGGCCCGGGUUCCACUUGGCGGCGUCUUCUCUCGAGUCGCCUUCGCUGCUCCGAGAAGUCGGCGGCGCAGCAGUUGACGCUCAGCUCGCCGCAGGUCGCCAUAUUCCCCGCGGAGGCCGGCUGGGCUCUCGCCUCAGGCCGCCCACCCUGCUCCGGCCGCCGCGGCCUCUCCGUUCCCGCAGCCAGAGGUGGGGAGAGAGCGACCUCCAGGCACUGGGCACCCGCCGCUUCCCCAGCAGCCGGCGGGGCGAUGGAGAAAGACGCCAGGAAGCGGAAGGUCCCCGCCGGCCCGAGGGUCGCCCGGGGCUGCGCCCCAUGGUUCCUGCCCACGGAGCAGCUGCCGGGACCCUCCCUGCCAAGUUGCUCCCGGAAAAGCUCUCAGGUUCUCAGGCCUGCAGGGAGUGACAGUUUCCCCCUGACUGGAACGUAAGGCUGCAAACUCGAAGCCAGGCAUUUUCUGCGUAUUCUUAAAUAGGAUGUUUCAGUCAAAGCCUUGAUAAUAUAACCAAUCAUUCUGAUUACAGCCUGCUUAUAAGGAGAACAUGUGUACAUCAAAUAGAGACGAGGUUUCACCGUGUUAGCCAGGAUGGUCUCGAUUUCCUGACCUCGUGAUCCACCCGCCUCGGCCUCCCAGAGUGCUGGGAUUACAGGUUUCAGGCACAGAACUGUAUAUCCAAUAAUAGUGAAAUGGAUCCCACUAAUUAUGACCGAAAUGAUGAUACAUUUAAAUGACUUGGAUGUUUUAUAGGUUGGCACUCAUCAUGAGCCCCUGUUCUCAUUCUGCAAAUGGUGAAGCUCUCUAUUGUCCUGACCCCACGGUUCCUGUCCCAUGACCAGGGCCAGCUCACCAAGGAGCUGCAGCAGCACGUAAAGUCAGUGACAUGCCCAUGCGAGUACCUGAGGAAGGUUGAUGGACGGAUGGCUACAUGGAUGUGAUGGAGAUGGUUUACUAUCGGGACCUUCCGCAUCCUGCUGAUGUUUUGUUGCUUAGGAUAUGAAUGGCUGAGCGGAGGCUGUAAAACCUGGCACUCUGCUUGGGUUAUCAAUACUCUGGCUGACCAUCGUCAUCGUGGGACUGACUUUGGUGGAAGUCCUUGGUUACUUAUCAUUACUGUGUUUCUGAGAAGUUAUAAAUUUGCCAUCUCCCUCUGCACAAGUUACCUUUGUGUGUCUUUCCUGAAGACUAUCUUCCCGUCUCAAAAUGGACAUGAUGGAUCCACGGAUGUACAGCAGAGAGCCAGGAGGUCCAACCGCCGUAGACAGGAAGGAAUUAAAAUUGUCCUGGAAGACAUCUUUACUUUAUGGAGACAGGUGGAAACCAAAGUUCGAGCUAAAAUCUGUAAGAUGAAGGUGACAACAAAAGUCAACCGUCAUGACAAAAUCAAUGGAAAGAGGAAGACCGCCAAAGAACAUCUGAGGAAACUAAGCAUGAAAGAACGUGAGCACGGAGAAAAGGAGAGGCAGGUGUCAGAGGCAGAGGAAAACGGGAAAUUGGAUAUGAAAGAAAUACACACCUACAUGGAAAUGUUUCAACGUGCGCAAGCGUUGCGGCGGCGGGCAGAGGACUACUACAGAUGCAAAAUCACCCCUUCUGCAAGAAAGCCUCUUUGCAACCGGGUCAGAAUGGCGGCAGCGGAGCAUCGUCAUUCUUCAGGAUUGCCCUACUGGCCCUACCUCACAGCUGAAACUUUAAAAAACAGGAUGGGCCACCAGCCACCUCCUCCAACUCAACAACAUUCUAUAAUUGAUAACUCCCUGAGCCUCAAGACACCUCCCGAGUGUCUGCUCACUCCCCUUCCACCCUCAGCUCUACCCUCAGCGGAUGAUAAUCUCAAGACACCUGCGGAGUGUCUGCUCUAUCCCCUUCCACCCUCAGCGGAUGAUAAUCUCAAGACACCUCCCGAGUGUCUGCUCACUCCCCUUCCACCCUCAGCUCCACCCUCAGUGGAUGAUAAUCUCAAGACACCUCCCAAGUGUGUCUGCUCACUCCCCUUCCACCCUCAGCGGAUGAUAAUCUCAAGAAACUAAGGAAGAAUAAAUAAAUAAUAUAAAAAUAAAAUGAAUACUGCAGUC